ACUGUACACAUGCUAGGGUCCAGGACAGCAGGACCAAGCCAGCAGAAACAGCCUGAGCCCACCGCAGACUGGCCUGGCUAUACUGGACAAUGCCACUCCUCCUGUACACCUGUCUUCUCUGGCUGCCCACCAGCGGCCUCUGGACCGUCCAGGCCAUGGAUCCUAACGCUGCUUAUGUGAACAUGAGUAACCAUCACCGGGGCCUGGCUUCAGCCAACGUUGACUUUGCCUUCAGCCUGUAUAAGCACCUAGUGGCCUUGAGUCCCAAAAAGAACAUUUUCAUCUCCCCUGUGAGCAUCUCCAUGGCCUUAGCUAUGCUGUCCCUGGGCACCUGUGGCCACACACGGGCCCAGCUUCUCCAGGGCCUGGGUUUCAACCUCACUGAGAGGUCUGAGACUGAGAUCCACCAGGGUUUCCAGCACCUGCACCAACUCUUUGCAAAGUCAGACACCAGCUUAGAAAUGACCAUGGGCAAUGCCUUGUUUCUUGAUGGCAGCCUGGAGUUGCUGGAGUCAUUCUCAGCAGACAUCAAGCACUACUAUGAGUCAGAGGUCUUGGCUAUGAAUUUCCAGGACUGGGCAACAGCCAGCAGACAGAUCAACAGCUAUGUCAAGAAUAAGACACAGGGGAAAAUUGUCGACUUGUUUUCAGGGCUGGAUAGCCCAGCCAUCCUCGUCCUGGUCAACUAUAUCUUCUUCAAAGGUAUUCCCACCCAUCCCCAUCUGAAGGCCCAUCCACUAUGGCCAGGAAUAACAGCCGCUAAAAUCCAGGGCACACUCUUGGGCAAAGUCUUUGAUUCUGUAAAGCACAUACACAUCUGGGAAUCUCCAUCUUCACCACAAUCCUGCUGGACCUGUCUCCUCCUCUUCCUAGGCACAUGGACACAGCCCUUUGACCUGGCAAGCACCAGGGAGGAGAACUUCUAUGUGGACGAGACAACUGUGGUGAAGGUGCCCAUGAUGUUGCAGUCGAGCACCAUCAGUUACCUUCAUGACUCGGAGCUCCCCUGCCAGCUGGUGCAGAUGAACUACGUGGGCAAUGGGACUGUCUUCUUCAUCCUUCCGGACAAGGGGAAGAUGAACACAGUCAUCGCUGCACUGAGCCGGGACACGAUUAACAGGUGGUCCGCAGGCCUGACCAGCAGCCAGGUGGACCUGUACAUUCCAAAGGUCACCAUCUCUGGAGUCUAUGACCUCGGAGAUGUGCUGGAGGAAAUGGGCAUUGCAGACUUGUUCACCAACCAGGCAAAUUUCUCACGCAUCACCCAGGACGCCCAGCUGAAGUCAUCAAAGGUGGUCCAUAAAGCUGUGCUGCAACUCAAUGAGGAGGGUGUGGACACAGCUGGCUCCACUGGGGUCACCCUAAACCUGACGUCCAAGCCUAUCAUCUUGCGUUUCAACCAGCCCUUCAUCAUCAUGAUCUUCGACCACUUCACCUGGAGCAGCCUUUUCCUGGCGAGGGUUAUGAACCCAGUGUAAGAGACCACCCACCCAGAGCCUCAGCACUGUCUGACUUUGGGAACCAGGGAUCCCACAGAAAUGUUUUGGAGAGCGGGAGGUUUCCCCCAAUCUCCUCCAAGUUCUUCUCCCUCCAACCAGAGUUGUGUCUAACUUUAGGCAUCUUUUAAUAAAUGUCAUUGCGACUCUGA